CUUCUUCCGCUGGAGGUAGUCAACCCCUGUACGCGGUUUCCUUCUCCUGCUCUCCUGCUUAUAGAACAAUUGUUCCUCCAGAACAAUUCCUCUCAGCCAUAGUGGCUCUGCUCCCACCAGAUGAUCUCUCAGCUCAUCCUGGUGACUUGCAGGGGUACAGGUCUGCCGGCUAUGUUGCCCAGGCUGGCCUCAAACUCCUGGCUUCAAUGAUCCUCUCAUCUUAGCCUCUUGAGUACUGGGACUAUAAGUGCCCACUGCCACGCCUGGCUGGUUAGGCUACUUUUCUGUGGAUCACAGCCCAUCAUCCACCAAUGCCUUGCCAACAACUGUAAAUGUCUCAUCCCUGAAUCCUGGAACUGAUAACAGCUCUGCCAGGUCUUCAGGUAAGGAGAGCAGGCCAACAGUCUGACUUCCAAGAUAAAUCUGCAGCAGGUGUUCAUCAGAACAGACACCAUGGCAGAGCAUGAUUACCAUGAAGACUAUGGGUUCAGCAGUUUCAAUGACAGCAGCCAGGAGGAGCAUCAAGACUUCCUGCAGUUCAGCAAGGUCUUUCUGCCCUGCAUGUACCUGGUGGUGUUUGUCUGUGGUCUGGUGGGGAACUCUCUGGUGCUGGUCAUAUCCAUCUUCUACCAUAAGUUGCAGAGCCUGACGGAUGUGUUCCUGGUGAACCUACCCCUGGCUGACCUGGUGUUUGUCUGCACUCUGCCCUUCUGGGCCUAUGCAGGCAUCCAUGAAUGGGUGUUUGGCCAGGUCAUGUGCAAGAGCCUACUGGGCAUCUACACUAUUAACUUCUACACGUCCAUGCUCAUCCUCACCUGCAUCACUGUGGAUCGUUUCAUUGUAGUGGUUAAGGCCACCAAGGCCUACAACCAGCAAGCCAAGAGGAUGACCUGGGGCAAGGUCACCAGCUUGCUCAUCUGGGUGAUAUCCCUGCUGGUUUCCUUGCCCCAAAUUAUCUAUGGCAAUGUCUUUAAUCUCGACAAGCUCAUAUGUGGUUACCAUGACGAGGCAAUUUCCACUGUGGUUCUUGCCACCCAGAUGACACUGGGGUUCUUCUUGCCACUGCUCACCAUGAUUGUCUGCUAUUCAGUCAUAAUCAAAACACUGCUUCAUGCUGGAGGCUUCCAGAAGCACAGAUCUCUAAAGAUCAUCUUCCUGGUGAUGGCUGUGUUCCUGCUGACCCAGAUGCCCUUCAACCUCAUGAAGUUCAUCCGCAGCACACACUGGGAAUACUAUGCCAUGACCAGCUUUCACUACACCAUCAUGGUGACAGAGGCCAUCGCAUACCUGAGGGCCUGCCUUAACCCUGUGCUCUAUGCCUUUGUCAGCCUGAAGUUUCGAAAGAACUUCUGGAAACUUGUGAAGGACAUUGGUUGCCUCCCUUACCUUGGGGUCUCACAUCAAUGGAAAUCUUCUGAGGACAAUUCCAAGACUUUUUCUGCCUCCCACAAUGUGGAGGCCACCAGCAUGUUCCAGUUAUAGGCCUUGCCAGGGUUUCGAGAAGCUGCUCUGGAAUUUGCAAGUCAUGGCUGUGCCCUCUUGAUGUGGUGAGGCAGGCUUUGUUUAUAGCUUGCGCAUUCUCAUGGAGAAGUUAUCAGACACUCUGGCUGGUUUGGAAUGCUUCUUCUCAGGCAUGAACAUGUACUGUUCUCUUCUUGAACACUCAUGCUGAAAGCCCAAGUAGGGGGUCUAAAAUUUUUAAGGACUUUCCUUCCUCCAUCUCCAAGAAUGCUGAAACCAAGGGGGAUGACAUGUGACUCCUAUGAUCUCAGGUUCUCCUUGAUUGGGACUGGGGCUGAAGGUUGAAGAGGUGAGCACGGCCAACAAAGCUGUUGAUGGUAGGUGGCACACUGGGUGCCCAAGCUCAGAAGGCUCUUCUGACUACUGGGCAAAGAGUGUAGAUCAGAGCAGCAGUGAAAACAAGUGCUGGCACCACCAGGCACCUCACAGAAAUGAGAUCAGGCUCUGCCUCACCUUGGGGCUUGACUUUUGUAUAGGUAGAUGUUCAGAUUGCUUUGAUUAAUCCAGAAUAACUAGCACCAGGGACUAUGAAUGGGCAAAACUGAAUUAUAAGAGGCUGAUAAUUCCAGUGGUCCAUGGAAUGCUUGAAAAAUGUGCAAAACAGCGUUUAAGACUGUAAUGAAUCUAAGCAGCAUUUCUGAAGUGGACUCUUUGGUGGCUUUGCAUUUUAAAAAUGAAAUUUUCCAAUGUCUGCCACACAAACGUAUGUAAAUGUAUAUACCCACACACAUACACACAUAUGUCAUAUAUUACUAGCAUAUGAGUUUCAUAGCUAAGAAAUAAAACUGUUAAAGUCUCCAAA